GGAAGUUCCGGGAGUGCCAAGUACCCGCGUGCAUACGGCUGCCGGCAUGGCACAUUACAACUUCAAGAAAAUUACGGUGGUGCCGUCCGCCAAGGUAGGCGGCCCCGGGAGGGCCACUGCAACUUUCGCGUUCUCCUCAGCUGGGUCCCCGGGGAGGGUCCGGGCCUGUAGCCGUGGGAGAGCGGUCGCCUUCCGCUCGCCCAUCCCCCGCUCCUGGGCCUGACCGUCUGGCCGCGUACUCGGGAUCAUUUCCCCUCCCCCAGCAGAAUCCGGGGUCCACCAGAGAUCGGAUCCCCCAGAGACCGGGGUCCACCUAAGACCGUGGUCCACCCAAAGACUGAGGGCCCCCAGAGAUGGGGGUACACCCAGAGUUGGGUUCCCUGGAGGGGCCCCGGGUGACGAUGUGGGCGAGUGGAGGGGGACCCCGACAUGUGAGGGAGGAAGCGUUCCGUGGUCCGUGAUGAGCCUUCGGAUUCUGGGUUUGGCGUAGCCCCCUCCCCUCUCAGGAAUCCUGGGACUUCAUAGACCUCACGUUGUCGAAGACUCAACGAAAGACUCCAACCGUUAUUCAUAAACAUUACCAAAUACAUCGCAUUAGACAUUUUUACAUGAGAAAAGUCAAAUUUACUCAACAGAAUUACCAUGAUAGACUUUCACAAAUUCUAACAGAUUUCCCCAAAUUGGAUGAUAUUCAUCCGUUCUAUGCUGAUUUGAUGAAUAUUCUCUACGACAAGGAUCAUUACAAGUUGGCUCUGGGGCAAAUAAAUAUUGCCAAAAAUUUAGUGGACAAUGUUGCUAAAGAUUAUGUGCGACUGAUGAAGUAUGGCGACUCUCUCUACCGCUGCAAACAGCUGAAGCGUGCGGCCCUGGGACGGAUGUGCACAGUGAUCAAGAGGCAGAAGCAGAGUUUGGAGUAUUUGGAGCAAGUGCGUCAGCAUUUAUCCCGUUUGCCAACCAUUGAUCCGAAUACCAGGACCCUGCUUUUGUGUGGGUACCCAAAUGUUGGGAAGUCCAGCUUCAUCAACAAGGUGACGAGAGCAGACGUGGAUGUCCAGCCCUAUGCGUUCACAACCAAGUCUCUGUUUGUUGGGCACAUGGAUUAUAAGUAUCUACGUUGGCAGGUUGUAGACACUCCUGGGAUCCUGGACCACCCUCUGGAGGAUAGGAACACCAUCGAGAUGCAGGCCAUCACUGCCCUGGCCCACCUCCGUGCUGCGGUCCUGUAUGUGAUGGAUUUGUCUGAGCAGUGUGGGCAUGGGCUGAGGGAGCAGCUAGAACUCUUCCAGAACAUCAGACCUCUCUUCAUCAACAAGCCUCUCAUAGUUGUAGCCAACAAAUGUGAUGUGAAGAGAAUAGCUGAACUUUCUGAAGAUGAUCAGAAAAUAUUUACAGAUUUGCAGUCUGAAGGAUUCCCUGUAAUAGAGACCAGCACCCUGACUGAGGAAGGUGUUAUUAAAGUUAAAACAGAGGCUUGCGAUAGGCUUUUGGCUCAUCGAGUGGAAACCAAAAUGAAGGGAAAUAAAGUGAAUGAGGUGCUGAAUAGACUGCACCUGGCUAUCCCAACCAGGAGGGACGAUAAGGAGAGGCCCCCUUUCAUCCCUGAAGGAGUGGUGGCUCGCAGGAAGAGGAUGGAAACUGAGGAGUCCAGGAAGAAGAGGGAACGAGAUCUUGAGCUGGAAAUGGGAGAUGAUUAUAUUUUGGAUCUUCAGAAGUACUGGGAUUUAAUGAAUUUGUCUGAAAAACAUGAUAAGAUACCAGAAAUCUGGGAAGGCCAUAAUAUAGCUGAUUAUAUUGAUCCAGCCAUCAUGAAGAAAUUGGAAGAAUUAGAAAAAGAAGAAGAGCUGAGAACAGCUGCUGGAGAGUAUGACAGUGUAUCUGAGAGUGAAGACGAAGAGAUGCUGGAAAUCCGACAGCUGGCAAAGCAAAUUCGAGAGAAAAAGAAGUUGAAAAUUCUGGAGUCCAAAGAAAAGAAUACACAGGGACCCAGGAUGCCGCGAACUGCUAAGAAGGUUCAGAGGACAGUUUUGGAGAAGGAGAUGCGUAGUCUUGGUGUUGACAUGGACGAUAAAGACGAUGCCCAUUACGCAGUCCAGGCAAGAAGAUCCCGGAGCAUCACUAGGAAAAGAAAGCGGGAAGACUCUGCUCCCCCGUCCUCUGUGGCCCGGAGUGGGAGUUGCUCUCGAACUCCACGUGACGUUUCUGGUCUUAGGGAUGUCAAGAUGGUGAAGAAAGCCAAGACUAUGAUGAAGAAUGCUCAGAAGAAGAUGAAUCGGUUGGGGAAGAAAGGGGAGGCGGAUAGACACGUGUUUGAUAUGAAGCCCAAGCACUUGCUGUCUGGGAAGAGGAAAGCUGGUAAAAAGGACAGGAGAUAGUAUCCGUUUGGUUGGCGUGGCUUCGCUAGAGUGUUGCUGUUUAUUUCCUGGUUUGGCACAGUAUGGUUUCAUGAAAUUGGAGCUCUGUAUAAACUGAAAAAGACAAAAUAAGUAAAGCACUUGUUGCUUUGCUGAAAACUAUGGUUAACCCUAUAUAGGUGUGGGAAAUUUUUGUCACUGCAUAAUAUUACAAAUAUUUUGAGUAGACAGUGUUUCCACAUUUAAUGGAGUAUCAGUUGCUUCAGAUUUUCAGAACUGGGAAGAUUUACUGGUUUAACUAGGUUGUUUUUGAUGGAGAAAAACCUUAUUUUCUUUUGUAAGAGCUGGGAGCAAACACGUUUAUGAGUGUGUCGGAAUCCCGUGCUUAAAAUACGCUCUUAAAUUAUUUUCUAGUCUUAUUUUACAAUGUCUCAUUGUAGUCUGUCUUCAACUAUUUUAUCCAAAAUAAACCUCCAGAAGAAAGUAGUUUUCAUUUACUUAGCUCAUGUUUUGGUUUAGUUAUAGUCGCUAUGGAUUUGGCCAAAUAAAAAGGCAAACAACAUGACAUUUCUAUUUUGUUUUAAAGCAAAAAUACUUUUGGGGGAGUAAAAUGUUGCUGGAGGCAUUAGGCAAUUAAAUAUGGGCAUUCUCCUAUUUCUGUGGCCCGUCCCUGAAGUUACAUGUUCAGUAAAACACAAAAACACCGCCAAUGCCACCUCAAAAGCACCUGCUGGGGAGCGUUGGGGUGAAGAGCUGUGGGGUCGGAGGGACCUGCCCAGGGGUCCGUGUGCUCCUGGAGCUCCAAAGACACACAGGGGUCCAAGAGCCACCACGGAUAAGUUAUCAAGUCACACAAUCAACAUUAUAGCUGAGGAAAGGACUUUAGUUAAUCACACUUCUGGAUUACAUGUGGCAAUUUUAAAAAUUUACCAGGGCUGGGCUGGGCGCAGGGGCUCAAGCCUGUAGUUCCAGCACUUUGGGAGGCCGAGGUGGGCAGAUCAGGAGGUCAGGAGUUCGAGACCAGCCUGGCCAACAUGGUGAAACCCCAUCUCUACUAAAAAUACAAAAAUUAGCCAUGCGUGGUGGUGGGCAUCUGUAAUCCUAGCUGCUCGGGAGGCUAAGGCAGGAGAAUUGCUUGAGCCCAGAGGCGGAGGUUGCAGUGAGCCGAGAUCGUGCCACUGCACUCCAGCCUGGGUGACAGAGAGAGACUCCGUGUGAAAAAAAAAAAAAAAAUACCAGGUCUGGUUUUUGAAAUUCUUUCUCCGUAUUAAACACCAAAACUUAACAUAUAGUUUACUUUGUGUUAAACAACAACAGUAUGGCCGGGCGCGGCAGCUCAUGCCUGUAAUCCCAGCACUUUGGGAGGCCGAGGCAGGCGGAUCACGAGGUCAGGAGAUCGAGACCAUCCUGGCUAACACGGUGAAACCCCGUCUCUACUAAAAAUACAAAAAAUUAGCUGGGUGUGGUGGCGGGCGCCUGUAGUCCCAACUACUUGGGAGGCUGAGGCAGGAGAAUGGCUUGAACCCGGGAGGCGGAGCUUGCAGUGAGCCAAGAUCGCACCACUGCACUCCAGCCUGGUCGACAGCGAGACUCCAUCUCAAAAAAAAAAAAAAAAUACCAGGUCUGGUUUUUGAAAUUCUUUCUCCGUAUUAAACACCAAAACUUAACAUAUAGUUUACUUUGUGUUAAACAACAACAGUAUGUUUUAAAGCAAGUAUGUCUUUAUUUGUAAGCAUAUUACUGAAACGAUCAAAUGAACAGAAGUGGAUAAACGUCGAGUCACUUGGCUGAGACCAUACGCAUCUUCCGUACUGCUUGUAUUAGGAUGCAAGAUUGAAUGUGUCUUUUUUUUAAAAAUGCAGCCUUGUGUUGCACUCUGAAAUAAGUGAUUUAAAAAGAAAAACAUGAUACAGAGAUCCCAUCCUGACCUUGGAGGCUUGGAUAAAGCUGUGGGGAGACAGCCUCAUGGUCCAGCCAGGCUAGUCCGCCUGCUUCAGGACUCUCAAGAUCUCCCCAAGACUUUCAGGAUCAGCUGCUGUUAAUCAAACAAGUGCUUAUAAAAUGGAAAUUGGGACAAAGGAAAUGUUAAAUUUCCUCCCUGCAACCAGGCAGAUGAGAAAUAUGGAAAUAAGGAAAAGGGAAAAUGAAGAUAUGACAAAGUUGAUGAAAAGGUUGAAAUAGUGAUUUAUACAUGAUGGGCAAUCAAGUGCCCCUUUUGCCCUGUUUUUUGGAGAGGGUGUAUCAUUGCCUCAAUGGUGCGUCUGCCUGCACUGAGGGCAUUACACAUGGCUGACUCGACCUCCCUGCCUCUCACACUCUGUGUAUUUUGUGAAGCUCCACAAACGGGGUCACGUCAUCCAGGUGAGGCCACCACCGGUACAGAAACCUCUCGGCAAUGGUUCUUAGCCAGGGGGUGACUUUGACUUCACCCCUCGCCUCCCUCUCCAGCAGCUCCCACAGCUCCUCCUGGGACAGGUAGAGGAUGCUUUUCGUUUCACUGGGAUCCGGGUUCAGAGUGACGUUUUUCCUCACAAGCAGAAGGUAACAAAUUUCAUGCUCUCCCCAAAUUCUGUCUGAUUUUGCCUUGUGGUGAUAGAUUGUCAUGAACACAAUGUCCUCUGGAGAAAUCUAUUGACAGAAAUUGGUGCAGUGUUAACAACGCUAAUGUAAAACACAGAAUUUACAGAAAAAUAGAGAAAAUAAACACAUUUGUUUUCCUCAGAAAA